ACAGUCCUCGGCCCAGGCCAAGCAAGCUUCUAUCUGCACCUGCUCUCAAUCCUGCUCUCACCAUGAGCCUCCGCCUGCAGAGCUCCUCUGCCAGCUAUGGAGGUGGUUUCGGGGGUGGCUCUUGCCAGCUGGGAGGAGGCCGUGGUGUCUCUACCUGUUCAACUCGGUUUGUGUCCGGGGGAUCAGCUGGGGGCUAUGGAGGCGGCGUGAGCUGUGGUUUUGGUGGAGGGGCUGGUAGUGGCUUUGGAGGUGGCUAUGGAGGUGGCCUUGGAGGUGGCUAUGGAGGUGGCCUUGGAGGUGGCUUUGGUGGGGGUUUUGCUGGUGGCUUUGUUGACUUUGGUGCUUGUGAUGGCGGCCUCCUCACUGGCAAUGAGAAGAUCACCAUGCAGAACCUCAACGACCGCCUGGCUUCCUACCUGGAGAAGGUGCGCGCCCUGGAGGAGGCCAACGCUGACCUGGAGGUGAAGAUCCGUGACUGGCACCUGAAGCAGAGCCCAGCUAGCCCUGAGCGGGACUACAGCCCCUACUACAAGACCAUUGAAGAGCUCCGGGACAAGAUCCUGACCGCCACCAUUGAAAACAACCGGGUCAUCCUGGAGAUUGACAAUGCCAGGCUGGCUGCGGACGACUUCAGGCUCAAGUAUGAGAAUGAGCUGGCCCUGCGCCAGAGCGUGGAGGCCGACAUCAACGGCCUGCGCCGGGUGCUGGAUGAGCUCACUCUGUCUAAGACUGACCUGGAGAUGCAGAUCGAGAGCCUGAAUGAAGAGCUAGCCUACAUGAAGAAGAACCAUGAAGAGGAGAUGAAGGAAUUUAGCAACCAGGUGGUCGGCCAGGUCAACGUGGAGAUGGAUGCCACCCCAGGCAUUGACCUGACCCGCGUGCUGGCAGAGAUGAGGGAGCAGUACGAGGCCAUGGCAGAGAGGAACCGCCGGGAUGCUGAGGAAUGGUUCCACACCAAGAGUGCAGAGCUGAACAAGGAGGUGUCUACCAACACUGCCAUGAUUCAGACCAGCAAGACAGAGAUCACGGAGCUCAGGCGCACGCUCCAAGGCCUGGAGAUUGAGCUGCAGUCCCAGCUGAGCAUGAAAGCGGGGCUGGAGAACACGGUGGCAGAGACGGAGUGCCGCUAUGCCCUGCAGCUGCAGCAGAUCCAGGGACUCAUCAGCAGCAUCGAGGCCCAGCUGAGCGAGCUCCGCAGUGAGAUGGAGUGCCAGAACCAAGAGUACAAGAUGCUGCUGGACAUCAAGACACGUCUGGAGCAGGAGAUCGCCACCUACCGCAGCCUGCUCGAGGGCCAGGACGCCAAGAUGAUUGGUUUCCCUUCCUCAGCAGGAAGCGUCAGCCCCCGUAGCACCUCUGUUACCACGACUUCUAGUGCCUCUGUUACCACCACCUCUAAUGCCUCUGGUCGCCGCACUUCUGAUGUCCGUAGGCCUUAAAUCUGCCUGGCGUCCCCUCCCUCUGUCUUCAGCACCCAGAGGAGGAGAGAGCCGGCAGUUCCCUGCAGGAGAGAGGAGGGGCUGCUGGACCCAAGGCUCAGUCCCUCUGCUCUCAGGACCCCCUGUCCUGACUCUCUCCUGAUGGUGGGCCCUCUGUGCUCUUCUCUUCCGGUCGGAUCUCUCUCCUCUCUGACCUGGAUACGCUUUGGUUUCUCAACUUCUCUACCCCAAAGAAAAGAUUAUUCAAUAAAGUUUCCUGCCUUUCUGCAAACAUA